AGAUUGGCCCUGGUGCCACGUCAGCCGGACUGAAGCUCUCCCUGCACCGCCUGCGGCCCUGCUGGCGUGGCACGGAUAUCACCCCCUCCCUCACCAGCCGCCGGCCCAGCUGGGGACAAGGGUGGCUCCCACCCAGGGAGGACCUCAGCCGCUGCUGGGAGCUCAGCCUCCCGCGAUGCCAUCGGGCGGGCACCCCCACCACGGCGCCUGCCCUCUGGAAGGAGCAGCAGAGGAAGGCCGCGGCUCUUCCCUGCCCUUGCCAGGCAGGUGUGCAGCUCCAAUUAAGGAACAGCUAUAUCCUGCUUCCUUCUGUAAGCAGCAUCGACUUGUGCAAGGGUUCAGUCAUGCAGCCACCGCCCCAGACGGUCCCGUCUGGCAUGGCUGGGCCACCUCCAGCCGGGAAUCCUCGGAGCGUGUUCUGGGCUAGCAGCCCUUACAGGAGACGGGCUAAUAAUAAUGCAGCAGUGGCUCCGACAACUUGCCCGUUGCAGCCGGUCACGGAUCCAUUUGCUUUUAGUAGACAGGCGCUCCAAAGUACACCACUGGGCAGUUCGUCCAAAAGCAGUCCACCUGUCUUGCAAGGCCCAGCCCCCGCAGGGUUUUCUCAGCACCCCGGUUUGCUUGUUCCUCACACACAUGCCAGAGAUAGCUCUCAGGGACCCUGUGAGCCCCUGCCUGGACCUCUGACACAGCCCAGAGCACAUGCCAGUCCGUUUUCUGGUGCAUUGACACCUUCAGCACCUCCUGGGCCUGAGAUGAACAGGAGUGCAGAGGUCGGUCCCAGUUCAGAGCCUGAAGUUCAGACUCUGCCAUAUCUUCCUCACUACAUUCCAGGAGUGGAUCCUGAAACGUCUCAUGGGGGCCACCCUCAUGGGAACAUGCCUGGGCUCGACCGACCCCUGAGCAGGCAAAACCCACAUGACGGUGUGGUCACCCCAGCAGCAUCCCCUUCCCUCCCUCAGCCUGGUCUGCAGAUGCCAGGACAGUGGGGGCCAGUGCAGGGAGGCCCACAGCCCUCGGGGCAACAUCGUUCACCCUGCCCUGAAGGACCUGUUCCCAGCGGGGUGCCCUGUGCCACCAGCGUUCCUCAUUUCCCCACCCCGUCCAUCCUACAUCAGGGCCCUGGUCAUGAGCAACACAGCCCUCUGGUGGCUCCCCCAGCAGCCUUGCCCAGUGACGGAAGAGACGAGGUGAGCCACUUGCAAAGUGGAAGCCACCUGGCCAAUAACUCUGAUCCUGAAAGUACAUUCAGGCAAAAUCCCAGAAUUGUGAAUCACUGGGCAAGCCCAGAGCUCAGGCAGAAUCCAGGAGUGAAGAAUGAGCACCGGCCCGCCUCUGCUCUUGUGAACCCCCUCGCCCGGGGAGAUAGCCCAGAAAACCGUACGCACCACCCACUGGGGGCUGGGGCCGGGUCUGGCUGUGCCCCGCUAGAAGCAGACUCAGGAGCUUCAGGAGCUCUGGCGAUGUUUUUCCAAGGGGGAGAGACAGAAAAUGAGGAGAAUCUCUCAUCUGAAAAAGCAGGCUUAUCUGGUCAAGCGGACUUUGACGAUUUCUGCUCCAGCCCUGGGCUAGGCCGUCCGCCCGCACCUACACACGUGGGGGCAGGCAGCCUCUGCCAGGCCCUUCUCCCAGGCCCCAGCAAUGAGGCUGCUGGUGAUGUGUGGGGUGACACAGCGAGCACAGGGGUGCCGGAUGCCAGCGGCUCGCAGUAUGAGAAUGUUGAGAACUUAGAAUUUGUUCAGAAUCAAGAAGUUCUGCCAAGUGAGCCCCUCAAUUUGGACCCUUCCUCCCCGAGUGACCAGUUCAGAUAUGGGCCCCUUCCUGGGCCAGCUGUGCCCAGGCAUGGUGCUGUGUGCCACACCGGAGCCCCUGAUGCCACACUGCAUACAGUGCACCCUGACAGCGUGUCAUCCAGCUAUAGCAGCAGAAGCCACGGAAGGCUCUCAGGCUCAGCCAGGCCCCAGGAGCUGGUUGGCACAUUCAUUCAGCAAGAAGUUGGAAAACCCGAGGAUGAAGCUUCAGGUAGUUUUUUUAAGCAAAUCGAUUCUUCUCCCGUAGGAGGUGAAACAGACGAGACCACUGUGAGCCAGAAUUACCGUGGCAGCGUGUCCCAGCCCUCAACCCCGAGCCCCCCGAAACCUACAGGAAUAUUUCAGACAAGUGCAAAUAGUUCUUUCGAACCGGUAAAAUCUCACUUAGUUGGGGUAAAACCAUUUGAGGCAGAUCGCGCCAACGUGGUUGGUGAAGUAAGGGAGACCUGUGUCCGCCAGAAGCAGUGCAGACCAGCUGCCGCCCUGCCCGAUGCUUCCCCUGGCAACCUGGAGCAGCCACCAGACAACAUGGAGACCCUCUGUGCACCCCAGGUCUGUCCCCUGCCUCUUAACUCCACCACGGAAGCUGUGCACAUGCUUCCGCACGCAGGGGCACCGCCCUUGGAUACUGUGUAUCCAGCACCCGAGAAGAGGCCUUCAGCCAGGACCCAGGGGCCCGUGAAGUGUGAGAGCCCAGCAACGACUCUGUGGGCGCAAAGUGAGCUGCCAGAUUUUGGAGGCAACGUCCUUCUGGCCCCUGCAGCCCCGGCGCUUUAUGUGUGUGCAAAACCUCAGCCACCUGUUGUUCAGCCUCCAGAAGAGGCGAUGUCCGGGCAGCAGUCACGGAACCCAAGCUCGGCGGCCCCGGUGCAGAGCCGAGGUGGCAUUGGUGCUUCUGAGAACCUUGAGAAUCCUCCCAAAAUGGGAGAGGAGGAGGCCCUUCAGUCCCAGGCGAGUUCUGGUUAUGCAAGUUUAUUAUCCUCACCGCCCACUGAGUCUCUGCAGAAUCCUCCAGUCUUGAUUGCUCAGCCUGAUCACAGCUAUAAUCUGGCUCAGCCCAUUAACUUUUCUGUGUCCUUAUCGAACUCUCAUGAGAAGAAUCAGUCCUGGAGAGAGGCUUUGGUGGGGGAUAGACCUGCAGUCAGCAGUUGGGCUCUCGGUGGUGAUUCUGGGGAGAACACUUCUUUGUCUGGGAUUCCAACCAGCUCUGUCCUUAGCUUGUCUCUGCCUAGCAGUGUUGCCCAAAGUAAUUUUCCACAAGGUUCUGGUGCUUCCGAAAUGGUUUCUAAUCAGCCUGCUAAUUUGCUGGUUCAACCACCAUCCCAGCCAGUUCCAGAGAACUUGGUUCCAGAAAGUCAAAAGGAUCGUAAGGCAGGAAGUGCUCUUCCCGGAUUUGCUAAUAGCCCUGCUGGAAGCACAAGUGUGGUGUUAGUUCCACCUGCACACGGCACCCUGGUGCCUGAUGGUAAUAAGGCAAACCAUUCCAGUCAUCAGGAAGACACUUACGGAGCCCUAGACUUUACCUUAAGCAGGACUUUGGAAAAUCCUGUAAACGUGUACAACCCGUCCCAUUCUGACAGCCUCGCUUCUCAGCAAAGUGUUGCCAGUCAUCCCAGACAAUCUGGGCCUGGGGCGCCUAACCUUGACCGUUUUUAUCAGCAGGUCACGAAAGAUGCCCAGGGCCAGCCUGGCCUCGAAAGAGCCCAGCAGGAGCUGGUGCCACCCCAGCAACAGGCUUCUCCCCCACAACUACCCAAAGCCAUGUUUUCGGAGCUGUCAAAUCCAGAAAGUCUGCCCGCACAGGGACAGGCCCAGAACUCAGCACAGUCACCAGCAAGUCUGGUUCUGGUCGACGCGGGUCAGCAGCUGCCCCCUCGGCCUCCUCAGUCCUCUAGCGUGUCUCUGGUGUCCAGUGGCUCCGGCCAGGCAGCUGUGCCGUCAGAGCAGCCGUGGCCACAGCCAGUGCCUGCACUUGCCCCCGGCCCACCGCCUCAGGACCUGGCCGCCUACUACUACUACCGGCCUUUGUACGAUGCCUACCAGCCUCAGUACUCUUUGCCGUACCCACCGGAGCCUGGCGCAGCCUCCCUCUAUUACCAGGAUGUCUACAGCCUCUAUGAGCCUCGAUACAGGCCCUAUGAUGGUGCUGCGUCUGCUUACGCCCAGAACUACCGCUAUCCCGAGCCCGAGCGGCCCAGCUCCCGAGCCAGCCACUCCUCGGAACGGCCACCUCCCAGGCAAGGAUAUCCUGAAGGAUACUAUAGUUCCAAAAGUGGAUGGAGCAGUCAGAGCGAUUACUAUGCAAGCUAUUACUCCAGCCAGUACGAUUAUGGAGAUCCAGGUCACUGGGAUCGUUACCACUACAGUGCUAGAGUCAGGGACCCCCGCACCUAUGACCGGAGGUAUUGGUGUGAUGCAGAGUAUGACGCAUACAGGAGAGAGCACUCUGCCUUCGGGGACAGGCCCGAGAAACGUGACAACAACUGGAGGUACGAUCCUCGCUUCACGGGGAGUUUUGACGAUGACCCCGAUCCGCACAGAGACCCUUAUGGGGAAGAGGUGGACCGGCGCAGCGUCCACAGCGAGCACUCGGCACGGAGCCUGCACAGCGCACACAGCCUGGCCAGCCGCCGCAGCAGCCUCAGCUCCCACUCGCACCAGAGUCAGAUUUACAGAAGCCACAAUGUGGCUGCCGGUUCCUACGAGGCCCCGCUUCCUCCAGGCUCCUUUCACGGCGAUUUUGCCUACGGCACCUACCGCAGCAAUUUCAGCAGUGGCCCCGGCUUCCCAGAGUAUGGCUACCCUGCCGACACCGUCUGGCCUGCCAUGGAGCAAGUUUCAUCAAGACCAACUUCUCCUGAAAAAUUUUCAGUGCCUCAUGUCUGUGCCAGGUUUGGCCCUGGCGGUCAGCUUAUCAAAGUGAUUCCCAAUCUGCCUUCAGAAGGACAGCCGGCCUUGGUGGAGGUCCACAGCAUGGAGGCCUUGCUGCAGCACACGUCUGAGCAGGAGGAGAUGCGGGCGUUCCCGGGACCCCUGGCCAAAGACGACACCCAUAAGGUGGAUGUCAUUAAUUUUGCACAGAACAAAGCUAUGAAAUGUUUGCAGAAUGAAAACUUAAUUGACAAAGAGUCUGCAAGUCUUCUUUGGAAUUUUAUUGUUCUCUUAUGCAGACAAAAUGGGACCGUGGUAGGGACCGACAUUGCGGAGCUUCUGUUACGAGACCACAGAACAGUGUGGCUUCCUGGGAAGUCGCCCAAUGAAGCAAACCUGAUUGAUUUCACGAAUGAGGCAGUGGAGCAGGUGGAAGAGGAGGAGUCUGGUGAGGCCCAGCUCUCUUUCCUCACUGGUGGUCCGGCGGCUGCCGCCAGCUCGCUCGAGAGAGAGACCGAGAGGUUCAGGGAGCUGUUGCUGUAUGGCCGUAAGAAGGAUGCUUUGGAGUCUGCAAUGAAGAAUGGCCUGUGGGGUCACGCUCUGCUACUUGCAAGUAAGAUGGACAGCCGGACACACGCCCGAGUCAUGACCAGGUUUGCUAACAGCCUCCCAAUCAACGACCCUCUGCAGACAGUCUACCAGCUCAUGUCCGGACGGAUGCCUGCCGCGUCCACGUGCUGUGGAGACGAGAAAUGGGGAGAUUGGAGGCCGCACCUCGCCAUGGUCUUGUCCAACUUGAACAACAACAUGGACGUCGAGUCCAGGACGAUGGCUACCAUGGGCGACACUCUGGCUUCAAGGGGCCUCUUGGAUGCGGCCCACUUCUGCUACCUCAUGGCCCAGGCGGGAUUUGGUGUUUACACGAAGAAAACUACAAAGCUUGUCUUAAUCGGAUCCAAUCACAGUUUGCCAUUCUUAAAGUUCGCAACCAACGAAGCAAUCCAGAGGACGGAAGCCUAUGAGUACGCCCAGUCCCUGGGUGCCGAGACCUGCCCCCUGCCUAGUUUCCAGGUGUUUAAGUUCAUCUACUCCUGCCGCCUGGCGGAAAUGGGGCUGGCCACGCAAGCCUUCCACUACUGUGAGGCCAUCGCGAAGAGCAUCCUGACGCAGCCGCACCUGUAUUCCCCGGUGUUGAUCAGCCAGCUUGUGCAGAUGGCUUCCCAGUUACGACUCUUCGAUCCCCAGCUGAAAGAGAAGCCAGAAGAGGAGUCCUUGGCCGCACCCACGUGGCUGGUUCACCUGCAGCAGGUGGAGCGGCAGAUUAAGGAGGGGGCUGGAGUAUGGCAUCAGGAUGGAGCCCUCCCGCAGCAGUGUCCUGGCACUCCGAGUUCCGAGAUGGAGCAGUUGGACAGGCCAGGACUCAGUCAGCCAGGAGCCCUGGGGAUCGCCAACCCUCUGCUGGCGGUGCCUGCACCGAGCCCUGAGCACUCGAGCCCGAGCGUGCGGCUGCUGCCCUCAGCUCCGCAGACGCUCCCUGACGGCCCAUUGGCCAGUCCUGCCAGAGUGCCGAUGUUCCCAGUGCCACUGCCCCCGGGGCCCCUGGAGCCGGGUCCUGGCUGUGUGACCCCAGGGCCUGCACUUGGCUUCCUGGAGCCCUCCGGGCCUGGCCUCCCACCUGGUGUGCCACCUCUGCAGGAAAGGAGACACUUGCUCCAGGAAGCCAGGAGCCCAGACCCAGGGAUAGUGCCGCAGGAGGCGCCUGUUGGAAACUCACUUUCCGAGCUAAGCGAAGAAAAUUUUGAUGGAAAAUUUGCUAAUCUGACCCCCUCGAGGACGGUGCCAGACUCGGAGGCCCCCCCAGGGUGGGAUCGUGCCGACUCGGGUCCCACGCAGCCACCUCUGUCUCUCUCACCCGCUCCCGAAACAAAGAGACCCGGACAGGCAGCCAAGAAAGAAACGAAGGAACCUAAGAAGGGUGAAUCCUGGUUCUUUCGUUGGCUACCUGGAAAGAAAAAGACAGAAGCUUAUUUGCCAGAUGACAAGAACAAAUCGAUUGUUUGGGAUGAAAAGAAAAACCAGUGGGUGAAUUUAAAUGAGCCAGAAGAGGAGAAGAAAGCCCCGCCCCCACCUCCAACCUCGAUGCCCAAGACUGUGCAAGCUGCCCCGCCUGCCCUCCCAGGGCCUCCUGGAGCCCCCGUGAACAUGUACUCUAGAAGAGCAGCAGGAACCAGAGCUCGCUACGUUGACGUCCUGAACCCAAGCGGGACCCAGCGGAGCGAGCCGGCUCUCGCUCCUGCGGACUUUGUCGCUCCACUCGCGCCACUCCCAAUUCCUUCUAACUUGUUCGUGCCAACCCCAGUGUCUUCAGUGAGACCCCAGGGACGUUCGGGACGGAAUGAUGGCCUCCUCGCUCUCUCAUCCCCAGAUGCAGAAGAACCACAGCUUCCAGACGGGACUGGCAGGGAAGGGCCUGCAGCAGCUAGGGGCCUGGCCAAUCCAGAGCCUGCCCCAGAGCCCAAGGUUUUAAGCUCUGCAGCGUCACUCCCUGGCUCUGAACUCCCCUCCUCCAGGCCUGAGGGUUCCCAGGGAGGAGAGCUUUCGCGCUGUAGUUCAAUGAGUUCAUUAUCACGUGAAGUGAGCCAGCAUUUUAAUCAGGCUCCUGGCGACCUCCCUGCUGCAGGGGGCCCUCCCAGCGGGGCCAUGCCCUUCUACAACCCUGCUCAGCUGGCACAGGCUUUGCGAGGGAGCAAGAGUGGAUGCCUGCAUUGGCCAGCUGUCUGCAACUGAGGUCCCCGCGUCCCAUGCAGUAGGCCAGGCCUGGCCACCACUUGUCCCUGGACUCUGGACAGCCAGGCUGGCUCUGCAGAGCAGCUCCAGGUCUCAUGGCCCUGAUGAAACCACGGCACCUCCUGGCCACCCUCACAGUAAACAUUGAUGGUUAAGGAUACAGUGCUUUCAAGGGAGCCCAGGACUUGGCACUGACUUGUCGGUUUCCAGAGGCUUUUGGAAACAAAAACGAAGCCUUCAGCUUGUCAGCGCCAAUGGCCCGUGUGGUUCAUUAUGUGGACCAGCCCCUGCCACGCUGCAGCCGAGCACUGCUCACCCUGGGGGCAGGCAUGCAGAGGUCAUGCUGUUGAUUUCAUUCCAGGCCUGCGCCACCUCCGGGAGCUCAAGGCUAGGGAGGAUUGGCCAGAGGAAGCACCUGGUGCUGAACUAGGCUUGCCCUGCUGUGAACUUGCACUUGGAGCCCUGACGCUGCUGUUCUCCCCGAAGAACCCGACCGACCUCCGCGAUCUCCGUCCCGCCCCCAGGGAGACACAGCAGUGACUCAGAGCUGGUCGCACACUGUGCCUCCCUCCUCACCGCCCAUCGUAAUGAAUUAUUUUGAAAAUUAAUUCCACCAUCCUUUCAGAUUCUGGAUGGAAAGACUGAAUCUUUGACUCAGAAUUGUUUGCCGAAAAGAAUGAUGUGACUUUCUUAGUCAUUUAGGAUGAUUUAAGGAUAUAGUAUUCCUGGUCAUUUAAGAAUGUUCAUUCAUUGAAGCCGGAGCUGUCUCUGCCACAGGAGAGCCACAUGGUCGGUAGUAACCAGGGCCUCUCCAAGCCCAGCUGUGAGUCACUGCCCAGUGAGUCCCGCGCUUCCUUUAAGGUGCUGGGAGCAAAGAGAGGGUGACUGAGGCAGACCCCAACCCCUGCUCUGCACCAUCUGGGCCCUCGCCGUGUUUGAACCUGGCUGAAUGAGUGGAGGGCGCUGUGUUCUCAAUCAGCGCCUCCGAGGAGCCGUGGGGUUCCUUCGGCAUUAGUUCACGGUUUUUGAGAGAGGCCUUAGUUACUGCAGUGAAUUUCUUUCCUGUUGCAAAGACGCUUCCAGCCUCACUUUACUUUCUGUGGCCUGAUGAGGACCAUGGGUGAUUUUGUGUACCCAAAGCGCUGGGGACUGCCCACCGUGUGGCCCAGUCACUGGGAAGGAGCCCCAGAGAGCCGGCUGUCUGACAUGAUGGCUCAGGGUGGUCAUCCAGGUUGAAAACUGACCGUGUGAUGUUUGAUUUGGGCUUCAUUUCGUGUGUAGGAGCACGGUUAGACUCACUGUUAAGGAAGCUGGAUGCACUUCUCUAAAAGGCUGCACUUUCCGUGAGCACUUUUCGUGGUACAAUCCACAUGACCCACUUUCUCCCCUGGGGGACGUUGGUUCAGAGGUUGGUAGCACUUGGGGAGAGUAUCUUAACACAGUUUCUUGACAGCAGCUCUGGAACUUAGUAUUUCUGCCCCGAGUUUUGCCACACUGAGACUUUGAGUAGCUCCUGGUGGACUCAACCCUGUUCAACUCAGAGACGGGCCUCCUCUCACUGAUGCAAAGCUUUAAGGCUUCUCUGACUGUUCUGAAACUCUUCGUAUUCUUGUCAAGUCUAAAGAGACUGAAGAAAAGAUUUAAAUACUAAUAAAAAUCAGUAGAUAAUUUCUGUAGGUUCUGCUGGAGGAAUACAAACUGUUUGGUGUUUUAAAUUUAAGUGUAGAAAUUGUAGAAUGUGGAAUUAGCACAGAUCCUUCCUGGCUUUCUGUUUCACUUGAUCAUUUAGCCCAGACCACCCAGGAUGUUUUCCAAAAUGUUCCACAGGCGUGUCCCGCUGGAUCCAUUUGUCCUUGUCACUUGGAGAAAGGCCAGUCCCUGUGACGGGGCAGCCCUCUCUGUCCCUCGGUCAGCUCGUGUGAAUCCUGGGACCUCUUCCGGUCGGCUCUGCCCGCUGUUCUGGGGUCGACUGCCACGACUUUUGAUUCAAGAAGCUUCCUCCAGGCGGGAGCGGCUAUUUUUCCUAAAUGAGAAUUGUUACAUUGCAAAUUGUUGAAUAAAAUAUUUUGCGCUCCUUCAA